ACUCAGCUCCUGCGCCGGGGGCGACAGAGCCGCAGGCGCCCGAGUCGAGUCCCAGCCAGCUACCAUCCCUCUGGAGCUUACCGGCCGGCCUUGGCUUCCCCAGGAAUCCCUGGAGCUAGCGGCUGCUGAAGGCGUCGAGGUGUGGGGGCACUUGGACAGAACAGUCAGGCAGCCGGGAGCUCUGCCAGCUUUGGUGACCUUGGGUGCUUGCCUCGUGCCCCUUGGUGCCCGUCUGCUGAUGUGCCCAGCCUGUGCCCGCCAUGCCGCCCUCCAUCUCAGCUUUCCAGGCCGCCUACAUCGGCAUCGAGGUGCUCAUCGCCCUGGUCUCUGUGCCCGGGAACGUGCUGGUGAUCUGGGCGGUGAAGGUGAACCAGGCGCUGCGGGAUGCCACCUUCUGCUUCAUCGUGUCGCUGGCGGUGGCUGAUGUGGCCGUGGGUGCCCUGGUCAUCCCCCUCGCCAUCCUCAUCAACAUUGGGCCACAGACCUACUUCCACACCUGCCUCAUGGUUGCCUGUCCGGUCCUCAUCCUCACCCAGAGCUCCAUCCUGGCCCUGCUGGCAAUUGCUGUGGACCGCUACCUCCGGGUCAAGAUCCCUCUCCGGAGAAUAAGCCAAUGCAUGGCAAGCACUAAAUCUUAGAUCCUGAAGACUCAGCCCUCGAGCAAAAGACAUGCACCUCCCCACUCACCGGGCCCUGGAAGAGGAGGGUGCUCCUCUUAGAGGCCCCUGGAGGCCAGGCGUGCCUCAGAGGGGCCUUUCGAGGCAGCUGGGAGGCAGAUCCUCACACUCUGCCCUCCUCUCCCCCAGGUACAAGAUGGUGGUGACCCCCCGGAGGGCGGCGGUGGCCAUAGCCGGCUGCUGGAUCCUCUCCUUCGUGGUGGGACUGACCCCUAUGUUUGGCUGGAACAAUCUGAGUGCGGUGGAGCGGGCCUGGGCAGCCAACGGCAGCAUGGGGGAGCCCGUGAUCAAGUGCGAGUUCGAGAAGGUCAUCAGCAUGGAGUACAUGGUCUACUUCAACUUCUUUGUGUGGGUGCUGCCCCCGCUUCUCCUCAUGGUCCUCAUCUACCUGGAGGUCUUCUACCUAAUCCGCAAGCAGCUCAACAAGAAGGUGUCGGCCUCCUCCGGCGACCCGCAGAAGUACUAUGGGAAGGAGCUGAAGAUCGCCAAGUCGCUGGCCCUCAUCCUCUUCCUCUUUGCCCUCAGCUGGCUGCCUUUGCACAUCCUCAACUGCAUCACCCUCUUCUGCCCGUCCUGCCACAAGCCCAGCAUCCUUACCUACAUUGCCAUCUUCCUCACGCACGGCAACUCGGCCAUGAACCCCAUUGUCUAUGCCUUCCGCAUCCAGAAGUUCCGCGUCACCUUCCUUAAGAUUUGGAAUGACCAUUUCCGCUGCCAGCCUGCACCUCCCAUUGACGAGGAUCUCCCAGAAGAGAGGCCUGAUGACUAGACCCCGCCUUCCGCUCCCACCAGCCCACAUCCAGUGGGGUCUCAGUCCAGUCCUCACAUGCCCGCUGUCCCAGGGGUCUCCCUGAGCCUGCCCCAGCUGGGCUGUUGGCUGGGGGCAUGGGGGAGGCUCUGAAGAGAUACCCACAGAGUGUGGUCCCUCCACUAGGAGUUAACUACCCUACACCUCUGGGCCCUGCAGGAGGCCUGGGAGGGCAAGGGUCCUACGGAGGGACCAGGUGUCUAGAGGCAACAGUGUUCUGAGCCCCCACCUGCCUGACCAUCCCAUGAGCAGUCCAGAGCUUCAGGGCUGGGCAGGUCCUGGGGAGGCUGAGACUGCAGAGGAGCCACCUGGGCUGGGAGAAGGUGCUUGGGCUUCUGCGGUGAGGCAGGGGAGUCUGCUUGUCUUAGAUGUUGGUGGUGCAGCCCCAGGACCAAGCUUAAGGAGAGGAGAGCAUCUGCUCUGAGACGGAUGGAAGGAGAGAGGUUGAGGAUGCACUGGCCUGUUCUGUAGGAGAGACUGGCCAGAGGCAGCUAAGGGGCAGGAAUCAAGGAGCCUCCGUUCCCACCUCUGAGGACUCUGGACCCCAGGCCAUACCAGGUGCUAGGGUGCCUGCUCUCCUUGCCCUGGGCCAGCCCAGGAUUGUACGUGGGAGAGGCAGAAAGGGUAGGUUCAGUAAUCAUUUCUGAUAUUUGCUGGAGUGCUGGCUCCACGCCCUGGGGAGUGAGCUUGGUGCGGUAGGUGCUGGCCUCAAACAGCCACGAGGUGGUAGCUCUGAGCCCUCCUUCUUGCCCUGAGCUUUCCGGGGAGGAGCCUUGGAGUGUAAUUACCUGUCAUCUGGGCCACCAGCUCCACUGGCCUGCCCGUUGCCGGGCCUGGACUGUCCUAGGUGACCCCAUCUCUGCUGCUUCUGGGCCUGAUGGAGAGGAGAACACUAGACAUGCCAACUCGGGAGCAUUCUGCCUGCCUGGGAACGGGGUGGACGAGGGAGUGUCUGUAAGGACUCAGUGUUGACUGUAGGCGCCCCUGGGGUGGGUUUAGCAGGCUGCAGCAGGCAGAGGAGAGUACCCCCCUGAGAGCAUGUGGGGGAAGGCCUUGCUGUCAUGUGAAUCCCUCAAUACCCCUAGUAUCUGGCUGGGUUUUCAGGGGCUUUGGAAGCUCUGUUGCAGGUGUCCGGGGGUCUAGGACUUUAGGGAUCUGGGGAAGGACCAACCCAUGCCCUGCCAAGCCUGGAGCCCCUGUGUUGGGGGGCAAGGUGGGGGAGCCUGGAGCCCCUGUGUGGGAGGGCGAGGCGGGGGAGCCUGGAGCCCCUGUGUGGGAGGGCGAGGCGGGGGAUCCUGGAGCCCCUGUGUCGGGGGGCGAGGGAGGGGAGGUGGCCGUCGAGUUGACCUUCUGAACAUGAGUGUCAACUCCAGGACUUGCUUCCAAGCCCUUCCCUCUGUUGGAAAUUGGGUGUGCCCUGGCUCCCAAGGGAGGCCCAUGUGACUAAUAAAAAACUGUGAACCCUG